GUCUUCCUGAGAGUCCGCGGGCUUCCGCUCCCAGCGCGGGAUUCUGGAGGGAAAUUGAGGGAGACUUGGAAACCGCGCCAGGCCCAACGGGUACCUAGAAGGGAGACAAAGCCAGGCCUGCUGCCCAGUUUGAGCUCUGGGAAGAAGAGGAGCAGGCCGGGACGCCCACCGAGGUAUCCCAGAGGUGACAGAACUUGAUCUGGGCCUGGAAGGGGAAGAAUUCGGGAAAAGCAACGUGGGGCAUUCCAGUAGUAAUUGAUAGAAAUAUUACGUGGGAUAGGAUUUAUUCUCUCCACACUUCUGAACCAAUGAAUAGAAAAUGGGAAGCAAAACUGAAGCAAAUUGAAGAACGAGCAUCUCAUUAUGAGAGGAAACCGUUGUCCUCAGUGUAUAGACCAAGAUUGUCCAAGCCAGAAGAACCACCCUCCAUCUGGAGACUAUUUCAUCGACAAGCUCAAGCUUUUAAUUUUGUUAAAAGCUGUAAAGAAGACGUUCAUGUAUUUGCUUUGGAAUGCAAAGUAGGAGAUGGACAACGUAUUUACCUUGUGACAACCUAUGCUGAAUUUUGGUUUUACUAUAAAUCCAGAAAAAAUCUCUUACACUGCUAUGAAGUUAUUCCUGAAAAUGCUGUGUGCAAGCUUUAUUUUGAUUUGGAAUUUAACAAACCUGCCAACCCAGGAGCUGAUGGGAAAAAGAUGGUUGCAUUACUCAUUGAGUAUGUGUGUAAAGCACUUCAAGAGUUAUACGGUGUUAAUUGCUCAGCUGAAGAUGUUUUGAACUUGGAUUCUAGCACUGAUGAAAAAUUCAGCCGGCAUUUAAUAUUUCAGCUCCAUGAUGUGGCAUUUAAAGAUAAUAUUCAUGUUGGUAAUUUUUUGAGAAAAAUUUUGCAGCCUGCUCUUGACUUGCUUGGCAGUGAAGAUGAUGAUAGCGCUCCAGAGACAACAGGCCAUGGAUUUCCCCAUUUUUCAGAAGCACCUGCAAGACAAGGAUUUUCUUUCAAUAAAAUGUUCACAGAAAAGGCUACAGAGGAAAGCUGGACAUCGAAUUCAAAGAAACUGGAGAGGCUGGGGUCAGCUGAGCAAAGCAGUCCUGACCUUUCAUUUCUAGUUGUGAAGAAUAACAUGGGAGAGAAGCAUCUUUUUGUAGAUCUCGGAGUUUAUACAAGAAAUAGAAACUUUCGGCUAUAUAAAUCAUCAAAAAUUGGAAAGCGUGUGGCUUUGGAGGUUACUGAAGAUAACAAAUUUUUUCCUAUACAGUCAAAAGAUGUUUCUGACGAAUAUCAAUAUUUUCUCUCUUCUUUGGUCAGCAAUGUCAGGUUCUCAGAUACUUUACGAAUUCUUACAUGUGAGCCAUCUCAGAAUAAACAAAAAGGAGUUGGAUAUUUUAACAGUAUCGGCACUUCAGUAGAAACCAUUGAAGGUUUUCAGUGUUCUCCCUAUCCUGAAGUUGAUCAUUUUGUUCUUUCUUUGGUGAAUAAAGAUGGCAUUAAAGGAGGAAUUCGGCGUUGGAACUACUUUUUCCCAGAAGAAUUACUGGUUUAUGAUAUUUGUAAAUAUCGGUGGUGUGAAAACAUUGGAAGAGCCCAUAAGAGUAAUAAUAUAAUUUCAUUUUGUGUGAUUUUUGGCAACCACCGUUUUGAUUGGAUUCUGGUUGAUCUGAAAAAUGAAGUUUGGUAUCAAAAAUGUCAUGACCCUGUAUGUAAAGCAGAAAACUUCAAAUCUGACUGUUUCCCAUUACCUGCUGAAGUAUGUCUCCUGUUUCUUUUCAAAGAGCUGGACUGUCCACUUGUUAAAAAAUUAAAUCCACCCUUGCUCUUCCGUCGGGGAGUAUUGAAAAGUAUGUGCACAGAACUGUAGGUAAUUUCAAAUUUGGAGUUUCAAGUGUGUCUGAGCUUCAGUGCAGCAACGUUUGAAUCAGUGCACUCAUUCCCACGGUGAGAUAUCGGAGACAGCAUUCCUCCUGCAUAUUCACUUUAGUAUCUGUCACUUAAUACCUUACUUCAACAUAGAGUAUAAGGUUAAAUCACAUAUCCUGAGUAAAUAUUUUCCUAUCCCACUCUCUAUCCCUUCACCACUGAAAUAAAGGAAGAAGAGUUUACAACAGAUGAAGCAGAUGAAACUAGGAGCAAUGAAACCCAGAAUCCUCAUAAACCAUCACCUAGCAGGCUGUCAACAGGUGCAUCUGCUGAUGCUGUCUGGGAUAAUGGCAUUGAUGAUGCUUAUUUUUUAGAAGCUACUGAAGAUGCUGAAUUAGCUGAAGCUGCAGAGAACAGUCUUCUCAGUUAUAACAGUGAAGUGGAUGAAAUUCCUGAUGAACUAAUUAUAGAAGUAUUACAAGAGUAACUAAUUCACUAUGAACACUUUUGUCACCAGGCUAUAAUUUGCCUGAUGUCUGUGAGAUUUGAUAAAUAUAUCAUUCAACCUGUUUAUAUAAACUAAGUUUUAUUACUUUGCUUUCCAAUUUUUGUUUUUUACUUCUGUAAACCAAUUUCAUUAAAAAUUAGCUUUGGUGUAAA